CUACUUCACGGAUCCGCUUCAAAGAGGCAGCUGCAGUGGAGAAUCAUGUUAAGCUCGGCUACUGCGGAGAGCCCAAGGUAGCCCAAUAAUGGAUUUUGAUGAGCGUGGUCCCUGCUCCUCUAACAUGUAUUUGCCAAGUUGUACUUACUACGUCUCGGGUCCAGAUUUCUCCAGCCUCCCUUCUUUUCUGCCCCAGACCCCGUCUUCGCGCCCAAUGACAUACUCCUACUCCUCCAACCUGCCCCAGGUCCAACCCGUGCGCGAAGUGACCUUCAGAGAGUACGCCAUUGAGCCCGCCACUAAAUGGCACCCCCGCGGCAAUCUGGCCCACUGCUACUCCGCGGAGGAGCUCGUGCACAGAGACUGCCUGCAGGCGCCCAGCGCGGCCGGCGUGCCUGGCGACGUGCUGGCCAAGAGCUCGGCCAACGUCUACCACCACCCCACCCCCGCAGUCUCGUCCAAUUUCUAUAGCACCGUGGGCAGGAACGGCGUCCUGCCACAGGCUUUCGACCAGUUUUUCGAGACAGCCUACGGCACCCCGGAAAACCUCGCCUCCUCCGACUACCCCGGGGACAAGAGCGCCGAGAAGGGGCCCCCGGCGGCCACGGCGACCUCCGCGGCGGCGGCGGCGGCUGCAACGGGCGCGCCGGCAACUUCAAGUUCGGACAGCGGCGGCGGCGGCGGCUGCCGGGAGACGGCGGCGGCAGCAGAGGAGAAAGAGCGGCGGCGGCGCCCCGAGAGCAGCAGCAGCCCCGAGUCGUCUUCCGGCCACACUGAGGACAAGGCCGGCGGCUCCAGUGGCCAACGCACCCGCAAAAAGCGCUGCCCCUAUACCAAGUACCAGAUCCGAGAGCUGGAACGGGAGUUCUUCUUCAGCGUCUACAUUAACAAAGAGAAGCGCCUGCAACUGUCCCGCAUGCUCAACCUCACUGAUCGUCAAGUCAAAAUCUGGUUUCAGAACAGGAGAAUGAAGGAAAAAAAAAUUAACAGAGACCGUUUACAGUACUACUCAGCAAAUCCACUCCUCUAAGACUCCAGCGGCUGGAAUUGGGUGGGGGGCUUCAUACACAUGAGAUAAUAUGCAGAUUUUGCCCUUGACAAAGUCAAGCCACAUGGUGACUUUUGAAAAGAGGUGUGCAAGAGAGGGAUGCAUGGAGAUAGCCCCACAGGAGGUGGUCUGGGACUCUCUUGAUUAAGAUCUCAGUGGUUAAGAUUCCUAAUAAUCAUUGGAUUCUGAGAGCUGUGCAUCAGCUAGAAUGACAGGUUUGGGACCCCUGGUGGUUCACUCUUGGAGCCUGCAGAGCUGCGGGCUGGGUGUGGUCUCCACUGGGGAUUGGGCCCCUGCCAGACCCCCUGGAGACUAACCCCACCACACCCUCCCUCUACUGGGAGCCUACCCACCCCCAGGACCCCUGAGUAAAAAAGCUGUGUGCUCUCCAAGCCCAGUUCAGCUUGGGGACAGGGGCAGGAGGAAGGGGUAGGAUUACUAGGUGCCCAGAAUGAGGCUGCUUUCCAAAGCCAAUGUGAACAGCGGCUGGACUUGGAGGUAGCUUUGAGGUGGAAGAGGGCUGCAAAUCCUUGUGGGAAAAGAAAUCUAUGAUUCCAGGUGGCAUCAGUGUCUUUCCACUCCUCCUAGCCACCCACCACACUGAUCCAGCCCUGAGUUCCUAGCCACCGCCUCCUACAGCCCACCUGGCUUUUCUUUCUACCAAAUGAGGGUCUUGGUUCCAGCCUGCCACUCAGGCCCAAAGCCUCGACACAGAGUGGACUGUUCCCUGAGGUGGGAGAUGUGGAAAAGCCAAGAGGCUGCAGCCAGGCCACUGGCCCCUGAGAUCUCUGCAGGAAAUGGCUGUGGAGUGUGGCAGUUUGGCAAACUCUCCACCACACGUAAUGAAACUUGGAUUUGCUCAGUGUCUGGCUGCAGAGCAGUGGGCCUGGCCAGCAGGUCCCCAGCUUUGGCUAUGAGGGCCUUGAGUCCCCCAAAACACCGGGUUCCAGCACCACACUCAGCCCUCAUUGGCUCUUGAACUGAGCUUGGAAGCUUCUGGUGACCUUCCAAGAGCCUGAGAGUGAGGUGGAAUUAUUUUAAAAGAUAAAUAUUAUAUUAUAUAUAUAUAUAUUUCCCUGAAGGAACCAAAGCGAAUUUUAAAAGAUGCAAUGUAGAGGGGAAAAGAGAUGAUGAAAAUAUUUAAAGGCCCUAUCUGUUUACAGUGUUCCGUGGUUAAACUCGCUCACUGCUAAGAAUAUUUGAAUGUAUGCUUCAUACAGGGAUGGUGUUCAAAAAACUUGUAAAUAAAGGAACCAUAAUCAAUUUUCUUUUCUUUCUUUCUCUUUUUCUUUUUUCUUUUGCCAUUAGUUGAUUUCCUUUAGGGUGUUGGAGGGGGUGGAAAAGGUAUUGAGAAUGGUCUUUUUAAUCUCUUGCAACAUUUGGAAAGAGUUAGGGAAAUGCUCAGAGGCAGUCGGCCUGGCCGGCCUGGGGAUCUCAUCUGGGAAAGCCAGGCACCCUCCCAUUGAAUCUCCUUUGCCUCCCUGUGUUAAGAAAUGUCUGUUGGCUCCAUUUGUACUGGGAGUGUUGGCCUGUCCUCAAUUCUGGUUCUUACCCACCGUGUGUGUUGCAGCACUUAUACAGGCAACUGGGCACAAGGAAAAUAAAGACGGUGGAAAUUUGA